AUCCUUGCUCUCCUCCCUCCUAGCCUACCCAGCUCGGGGUUCUGUCCCCGCCCAGAGACCUGAGGCUCGGGGCUGCAGAUGGAAUGCACGGCAGGGAGGCGGGACCCUUUGUUUGUGUGUGCGUGUUGUUGGCCUCCAUCCCCACUCCCCAGACUCCACUUCUCCAGGCCUCUCUCCCGCCUUUUCAUCCCGCAUCCGCAGGACACCCAAUCACCGGGCAACAGUUUCUCCCGUACAUCCCAGUCCAGCCCCAGCCUCUGGAGUUAUCUUUCUACACCAUGGAUCUGAUCACAGUACACCUGCUUUACGGAUGUCCAAGCCUCCUCCAUGGUAAAGUCCUCCCUUCCUACCCCUUACUGAGGCUGCUGGGGCUUUUCUCAAUUUGAGCCCCAUCUACCGCCGGCCUCAUUGGAGCCAUUCUUUGAACUUCAUUCAUUCAUUUGUGUCUUCAACACAUGUUUUUAUGUUUUUUCAGGACCUACCCUGGCUGGUACUGUGCUGGGAGCCGCUGGGGACCCCAGGCCCUGGCCGGUCCACGCUUCUCAGCCACCCUACACAGGCCACCCAUACGUGCUCCCUUUUAGGGCCUGAACCUUCAAAGCCUCUGUGAGAUACUCCCUGGUUCUGCCUUUCAGCUAUCACUCCCUGCUCCGAGCUCCACACCCUUUACAAAUGUUCAUUAAAGUUAUCUAUAUGGUAUGUUAAUCCAUUUCUGAGAAAAUAAUUUUCUUGGUUCCAUUUCCGUCAACGUUUGACAGUCCUCAAGGCCACCAUACUCUCUGGAGGUCUUGCUUCAUCCUCUUAUUUUGUACAGAAGGCUUUUGUUUGGGAUGUCUGCUCACACUCAAAGACAGAGAGGCCUUACUGUCUUUAUGUCUGCAGUCUGUGGAGUGAAUGAAGGAUGCUCAGGGCUGACACCAGCAUGAAAUGUGAUGGGAGAGGUUGGGGACUGUGUGAAUGUGAGGAAAGGGAGCCCAUCUGCCCCCCCAAGUACAACCCCACCAGUUGGGCAGAGUGAUCCCCCCACCACCCCUGCAUUGCUGUGAAAUUUAGAUUGGGCAGGGCCCGUUUGACCAUCUCUCUCAAUCUCAGGCUCUCCAUUUUCAAGUGAGAUGUAAUAAUAUGCGUCCUGUUUACCUCUCAGCCUGUGAUGAGAAUCUAAUGAUUAGGGUGUGCUAGCACACAGGCACCUGUAAAUCCCAUUGAAAUCUGAGGGCCCUAUAACUCCUCUAGUGAUUCCCAAGCCUCGUGCACCCCACCCUCUCUGUUCAUCCUUACUUCCCACGUGUCCCGUUAGCCCUCCGGAUGCAGUCAGGCCCAUUUCCCCCAGGACGCCCGGCACUAAGCCGCCCCAUCCAGCUGGGGUCUGAGGGGCCUGUCUCUUGCCCCACGCCUAAAAGACCUAACCCUCCUCCUAUCCCUUCGAUACGGCAGUCUUUAUUUGCUGGAGUCUGCACAACAUCACUGCCCAAUGAUGUGUCUGCUUCCACGAUUCCCAAAGAGACUGAGCUUACUGAGACCAGGGCAAGGACCGCGCCAGUUCCUCAUCGCCCCCUUCCUCUGCCUUCCCCUCCCUUCCCCCUCACCGCAGCCAUGGCGCCCAGACCAAGAAAGCAGAGCAGAGGUUCCGCAAUUCUUUUCUAAGAUUGUCUGACUAGAGGGUUCAAAGCCCUCUAAUCCAAGGCCGGCUUGUGUCUCUAGGGAGGUUGCAGAAAGGCGCCAGAAUGUGGAUGGCGCGGACAAUGUGGGAUACUGGAGUCUCGACUGCCGCGCGCCAAGGAAGGGCGUCACCUAGCCAAGCCGGCCCUGGAGUUGAGUGCCCCGCAGCCCGCCGGUCCACCCGCCCGGCCGCUUGCUGGCACCCUGGUGGCCGCGCCGGCUUUGUGUCGGCAUCAGGUGCAAACCCCCAGAGCGCCGGGCGUGCGCGCACGCGCCCCGGAGCGCGCGGAGCCCAUUCGUUGCCCCCACCGGGAUCUCCUCUAGGAUCUCCUCCGGCGCCCGGGGCCGGAGAGUGGGGGAGGGAGGAGGUCGGACACGUAGCCUGCCUCGCAGCAGGGCUCGACUCCACGCGGGAGGGCGGGGGAGCCGGGGACCCGCCGCUCCAGCCCGCUGGCCUUCGAAAGAUCCUCCUGGGCCAAUGGCAGGCGGGGCGACGCGACCGGAUUGGUGCAGGCGCUCUGCUGAUCGCUGUGGAAACUCGGGCGGCGGGGAACGCGGGAGGAUGUGGAACCCGAGGCGGGGGGAGCCGGAGGGGCGGGCAGAGGAGGUGUCGAGGCCCUGAGCUCCCGGGGAGUUUUUACUGGAGGCAAAAGUCCAUAGCGGGAGGGCUGAGGGAGGGGCGGAGGAAGGGGACCGCUUGGGGGCACUGGGAAGCCAGGGAUCCUCCGCCAGGAAGGCAGGGACACUCCCGAGCGCAGGCGAGAAGGCUGGGGGAGGGGGCGCGGUGGGAGGAGUAGGAGAAGACAAAAGCCGAAAGCGAAGAGGGCCCGGGCUGCACACACCGGCUGGGAGGCAGCCGUCUGUGCAGCGAGCAGCCGGCGCGGGGAGGCCGCAGUGCACGGGGCGUCACAGUCGGCAGGCAGCAUGGGGAAGGGAGGGAACCAGGGCGAGGGGGCCGCCGAGCGCGAGGUGUCGGUGCCCACCUUCAGCUGGGAGGAGAUUCAGAAGCAUAACCUGCGCACCGACAGGUGGCUGGUCAUUGACCGCAAGGUUUACAACAUCACCAAAUGGUCCAUCCAGCACCCGGGGGGCCAGCGGGUCAUCGGGCACUACGCUGGAGAAGAUGCAACGGAUGCCUUCCGCGCCUUCCACCCUGACCUGGAAUUCGUGGGCAAGUUCUUGAAACCCCUGCUGAUUGGUGAACUGGCCCCGGAGGAGCCCAGCCAGGACCACGGCAAGAACUCAAAGAUCACUGAGGACUUCCGGGCCCUGAGGAAGACGGCUGAGGACAUGAACCUGUUCAAGACCAACCACGUGUUCUUCCUCCUCCUCCUGGCCCACAUCAUCGCCCUGGAGAGCAUUGCAUGGUUCACUGUCUUUUACUUUGGCAAUGGCUGGAUUCCUACCCUCAUCACGGCCUUUGUCCUUGCUACCUCUCAGGCCCAAGCUGGAUGGCUGCAACAUGAUUAUGGCCACCUGUCUGUCUACAGAAAACCCAAGUGGAACCACCUUGUCCACAAAUUCGUCAUUGGCCACUUAAAGGGUGCCUCUGCCAACUGGUGGAAUCAUCGCCACUUCCAGCACCACGCCAAGCCUAACAUCUUCCACAAGGAUCCCGAUGUGAACAUGCUGCACGUGUUUGUUCUGGGCGAAUGGCAGCCCAUCGAGUACGGCAAGAAGAAGCUGAAAUACCUGCCCUACAAUCACCAGCACGAAUACUUCUUCCUGAUUGGGCCGCCGCUGCUCAUCCCCAUGUAUUUCCAGUACCAGAUCAUCAUGACCAUGAUCGUCCAUAAGAACUGGGUGGACCUGGCCUGGGCCGUCAGCUACUACAUCCGGUUCUUCAUCACCUACAUCCCUUUCUACGGCAUCCUGGGAGCCCUCCUUUUCCUCAACUUCAUCAGGUUCCUGGAGAGCCACUGGUUUGUGUGGGUCACACAGAUGAAUCACAUCGUCAUGGAGAUUGACCAGGAGGCCUACCGUGACUGGUUCAGUAGCCAGCUGACAGCCACCUGCAACGUGGAGCAGUCCUUCUUCAACGACUGGUUCAGUGGACACCUUAACUUCCAGAUUGAGCACCACCUCUUCCCCACCAUGCCCCGGCACAACUUACACAAGAUCGCCCCGCUGGUGAAGUCUCUAUGUGCCAAGCAUGGCAUUGAAUACCAGGAGAAGCCGCUACUGAGGGCCCUGCUGGACAUCAUCAGGUCCCUGAAGAAGUCUGGGAAGCUGUGGCUGGACGCCUACCUUCACAAAUGAAGCCACAGCCCCCGGGACACCGUGGGGAAGGGGUGCAGGUGGGGUGAUGGCCAGAGGAAUGAUGGGCUUUUGUUCUGAGGGGUGUCCGAGAGGCUGGUGUAUGCACUGCUCACGGACCCCAUGUUGGAUCUUUCUCCCUUUCUCCUCUCCUUUUUCUCUUCACAUCUCCCCCAUAGCACCCUGCCCUCAUGGGACCUGCCCUCCCUCAGCCGUCAGCCAUCAGCCAUGGCCCUCCCAGUGCCUCCUAGCCCCUUCUUCCAAGGAGCAGAGAGGUGGCCACCGGGGGUGGCUCUGUCCUACCUCCACUCUCUGCCCCUAAAGAUGGGAGGAGACCAGCGGUCCAUGGGUCUGGCCUGUGAGUCUCCCCUUGCAGCCUGGUCACUAGGCAUCACCCCCGCUUUGGUUCUUCAGAUGCUCUUGGGGUUCAUAGGGGCAGGUCCUAGUCGGGCAGGGCCCCUGACCCUCCCGGCCUGGCUUCACUCUCCCUGACGGCUGCCAUUGGUCCACCCUUUCAUAGAGAGGCCUGCUUUGUUACAAAGCUCGGGUCUCCCUCCUGCAGCUCGGUUAAGUACCCGAGGCCUCUCUUAAGAUGUCCAGGGCCCCAGGCCCGCGGGCACAGCCAGCCCAAACCUUGGGCCCUGGAAGAGUCCUCCACCCCAUCACUAGAGUGCUCUGACCCUGGGCUUUCACGGGCCCCAUUCCACCGCCUCCCCAACUUGAGCCUGUGACCUUGGGACCAAAGGGGGAGUCCCUCGUCUCUUGUGACUCAGCAGAGGCAGUGGCCACGUUCAGGGAGGGGCCGGCUGGCCUGGAGGCUCAGCCCACCCUCCAGCUUUUCCUCAGGGUGUCCUGAGGUCCAAGAUUCUGGAGCAAUCUGACCCUUCUCCAAAGGCUCUGUUAUCAGCUGGGCAGUGCCAGCCAAUCCCUGGCCAUUUGGCCCCAGGGGACGUGGGCCCUGCAGGCUGCAGGAGGGCACUGGAGCUGGGAGGUCUCGUCCCAGCCCUCCCCAUCUCGGGGCUGCUGUGUGGACGGCGCUGCCUCAGGCACUCUCCUGUCUGAACCUGCCCUUACUGUGUUUAACCUGUUGCUCCAGGAUGCAUUCUGAUAGGAGGGGGCGGCAGGGCUGGGCCUUGUGACAAUCUGCCUUUCACCACAUGGCCUUGCCUCGGUGGCCCUGACUGUCAGGGAGGGCCAGGGAGGCAGAGCGGGAGGGAGUCUCAGGAGGAGGCUGCCCUGAGGGGCUGGGGAGGGGGUACCUCAUGAGGACCAGGGUGGAGCUGAGAAGAGGAGGAGGUGGGGGCUGGAGGUGCUGGUAGCUGAGGGGACGGGCAAGUGAGAGGGGAGGGAGGGAAGUCCUGGGAGGAUCCUGAGCUGCUGUUGCAGUCUAACCCACUAAUCAGUUCUUAGAUUCAGGGGAAGGGCAGGCACCAACAACUCAGAAUGGGGGCUUUCGGGGAGGGCGCCUAGUCCCCCCAGCUCUAAGCAGCCAGGAGGGACCUGCAUCUAAGCAUCUGGGUUGCCAUGGCAAUGGCAUGCCCCCCAGCUACUGUAUGCCCCCGACCCCCGCAGAGGCAGAAUGAACCCAUAGGGAGCUGAUCGUAAUGUUUAUCAUGUUACUUCCCCACCCCUACAUUUUUUGAAAUAAAAUAAGGAAUUUUAUUCUCA